CCUCUCCCAGCCCCAGCAAGCAAACCGUCAGGCGGCCGUGGACUCAGAUCCCGGAGAUGAAGCCCCUGCUCCUGGCCGUCAGCCUCGGCCUCAUUGCUGCCCUGCAGGCCCACCACCUCCUGGCCUCAGACGAGGAGAUUCAGGAUGUGUCAGGGACGUGGUAUCUGAAGGCCAUGACGGUGGACAGGGAGUUCCCUGAGAUGAAUCUGGAAUCGGUGACACCCAUGACCCUCACGACCCUGGAAGGGGGCAACCUGGAAGCCAAGGUCACCAUGCUGAGUG